GUUGCGGAAGUGAUAGCCGCCGACCGAGCCUGCUGCUUUCUUGCUACUGCUUCGGCUUCCCGGCUACCCCCCGGACGGUGAAGGCGGCCCAGCUGUGGAUGGUCAGAUAGCCCUUGUCUCCCGCCGCCAAUCUCUGGCCCCUAGCAGCACGGAGCAGACGGCGGCAGCAGCAGCAGCAGGCGAGGAGGAAGAUGGCGGGACGGCUGCCGGCCUGUGUGGUGGACUGUGGCACGGGGUAUACAAAACUAGGAUAUGCUGGAAAUACAGAACCACAGUUUAUCAUCCCUUCCUGUAUUGCUAUUAAGGAGUCAGCAAAAGUGGGUGAUCAAGCUCAAAGGAGGGUGAUGAAAGGUGUUGAUGACCUAGACUUCUUCAUUGGUGAUGAAGCAAUAGAAAAACCUACAUAUGCAACAAAGUGGCCAAUCCGCCAUGGUAUAGUUGAAGAUUGGGACUUAAUGGAAAGGUUUAUGGAGCAAGUGAUCUUUAAAUAUUUAAGGGCAGAACCUGAAGACCAUUAUUUUCUUUUGACUGAACCUCCAUUGAAUACUCCAGAAAACAGGGAAUAUACUGCUGAAAUAAUGUUUGAGUCCUUCAAUGUUCCAGGCUUGUACAUUGCUGUGCAGGCUGUUCUUGCCUUAGCUGCAUCUUGGACCUCAAGACAAGUAGGAGAACGGACGUUGACCGGUACGGUAAUAGACAGUGGAGAUGGUGUCACUCAUGUCAUUCCUGUGGCUGAAGGGUAUGUGAUUGGCAGCUGUAUUAAACACAUUCCAAUCGCAGGACGAGAUAUAACAUAUUUUAUUCAGCAACUGCUGAGAGACCGAGAAGUAGGAAUCCCUCCAGAACAAUCCUUGGAAACUGCUAAGGCAGUAAAGGAGCGCUAUAGUUAUGUCUGCCCAGAUUUAGUAAAAGAAUUUAACAAGUAUGAUACAGAUGGGUCAAAAUGGAUUAAACAGUAUACUGGAAUCAAUGCUAUCUCAAAGAAAGAGUUUUCUAUCGAUGUUGGUUAUGAGAGAUUUUUGGGACCUGAAAUCUUUUUUCAUCCAGAGUUUGCUAAUCCAGACUUUACACAACCUAUCUCAGAAGUUGUAGAUGAAGUAAUUCAGAAUUGUCCUAUUGAUGUCAGACGUCCUCUCUACAAGAAUAUUGUCCUCUCUGGAGGUUCAACCAUGUUCAGGGACUUUGGACGUCGCUUGCAAAGAGAUUUGAAAAGAACUGUAGAUGCCCGGCUGAAAUUAAGUGAGGAAUUGAGUGGUGGUAGAUUGAAGCCAAAACCUAUUGAUGUACAAGUCAUUACACACCACAUGCAGCGAUAUGCAGUUUGGUUUGGAGGAUCAAUGCUGGCUUCCACGCCUGAGUUCUACCAAGUAUGCCACACCAAAAAGGAUUAUGAAGAAAUUGGACCUAGCAUUUGUCGUCACAAUCCAGUGUUUGGAGUCAUGUCGUAAAAUUGGCUUCAUAGUUAUUGGGGUUAGGGAGGUGGGGAAGAGAUAAUCUUUCUGAUUACCUGUUUUGUCUGGAUGGCUGGUUUUGAGGUUUUAAACCUGACUUGAAAUAGUAACACCAAACAUGAUUAUACAGGAAUAUUUUAAUAAGUGUAUCACCAUGCAGAUGUAGAAGAGAGCGAAAGUGAUUGUGUUUUUCUUUAGAUUGAAUAUUUGAAUCUUAUGUGUAACAAAAAGAAGUGGGUUUUAGUUCUUUCUGUGCCCUGAUAUUUUGUAUAUUAAUGAAUUAUCCAAGAUUCGAUGGGAUUUAUCAGUGUGUAGAUAGCUCUAUAAUGCUUGAAUUGUACACUUCUAAGUGUGCAGUGCAAGAGCUUGUUUAUAUUUCAUACUUUUUAUACUUUGAGGAAAAAAAGUCAAAGAAAAAUUGUAUUUGAGGGAAAAAACCAUGACCAAGUAAAGGAUAAAUUCAAAAAAUAGCCUCAUGAGACUUGGCAUACACACUCGUGGGAUUCCAGUUAUUAUGGAGUGCUUCCAUCCCUCUCCACCCCUUCCCCCCAAAAGGUUUUCUUUGCAAGUGCUUUUGGAACUAAGAGCUAGUAUCUUGGAUUAACUGAUGCCUGCUAGUGCUUUCUGAUUACUCGCAUUCUGUUUCUUGCUUUAAAAGAAGAGUAAAGACAAGAGUGUUGGACCAGUAUUGCAGUUCUGUAGUGUCAUUUCUUAUAAAAAACAAAACAACAACAAUAAUUUAUCAAAAUUGGCAUAUUUAAAGCCUAACAUUCUAAUAAAGGCACAAAUUUCUUUUUAAUACUUGUUUCAGCCUCUUUAAUCUCUUUAUAAGUUAACUAAUAAAUCUAUUUUCUUCAGACUUCUGCAAUAGUUCUUUAAAAUCACAACAGUUAGCAAGCUGACUUUUGUAAUGUGCUCAAUACAAAUACUUGUGAACUUUUAAUAUGUUGAGUGCUUUCAUUUUGAUAACUGGAUCUCCAUUUGAUAUUUUCAUUUGUAUAACUCAUUUGCAGUCUGAAAAUUUUUUUUAGUGCCAGUCCCUGAACAUAUCAUUGAAAGUUAAUUUUCUUUGCAUUUUAAAAUAUCUGGAUUAUGAAGAAAAAGUGAUGAAAAUAAAUUAAAACUGAAUUACCUUUUCUAAUGUUUUUUUUUUUUAAGUAAUGUAAUUCUAUUUUGUUUUUAUGUAUGUGAUAUCUGUUUCUGUUGAGAUUUGGGAGUUAUUGAAAUCUCUGUAAUGUGUAUGGUAGAAAAUUUCUUGUGACCUUAAAAUUUUACCAGUUAUUUAUAGAAAGAGAAAAUGGGAAAUGUUUUAUAGGCUUUUUACUAGCAGUAUCAGUGAACACUUGAACUCCAUUAUUCAUGAAAAUAACACGUUAGGAUUGGAAUACGUCUAUUCAAAAGUGAAAGAAUAUAAAGUGUUUAGUUUUUUGUUUUUACUCUAAAGAUAGAAUUGGGGAGUAAACUUCAGUUUUUGUUUAGAGUGGAUCUGAAUAUUUAAAAUCCUAUAAUAAUUUUUGUGAAUCUUCAUUCUUUGAGUAUGGGAUUGUAAAAGACAAACUAUAUCCUACAGUAGUAUCAUCAUCAGUAUCAAAGGUCUCCUUUUUUUACUUGGAAAAGUAAUUCACAAACAUUAUAAAAAUACUAUUCAAACAGUACCAAAGAGUAGAUUAGCAAAAGUAAGUUUUUUUCCCUAGCCUGUCUCAUUUUUCCAUCAUUACACAGACUACUUGGAAUGUCUUAGAUGUCCUUGUAUUGUAAUUUUCUGUGUAGGUAGAAAUAAAUGUAGCUUUCUUAUUUUACACAAAUAGGAACUUACUGUAUAUACUGUUCUGCACUUUGCUUUUAUUAAAGAUCUUUUGAUAAAGAACUAUAUUGAUAAGCAGUAAAGAUGUCAUGCUCCUGGCCCAAUAAAAUAUUGUUAGCAUUGUCAUAAAUAUGUCUUUUCCACCGGCGAUGGUUGGGUAGUUAAGUGAAUAAGCUAGAAAGACAUGUUUAUAAAGCUAUUUGAUGACAAUCUCAGGCAUAUUUAUACAGAGAUGUUCUUAACUGUUUGCUACAAAAACAUGAAGAUCAAAAACUUUCUUGAAGCUUACGCUUAACUUAUUUGGGGAAACAAAACUCCAGCCCUUCUUGUGUAUGUUCUGAUAUCCCUUUGCUCUACUUUUAGAGGAGUGAACCCUAAUAGGAUGGUAGCAGCAUUCUUGUUUCUUUAUAUCUCUCCUCUGUGAUUGUAUACCGUUUUUUCAACUUAAAGCAACUUCAGCUGGAAAUAUGUAGAGGUUGGCCAAGGUGAACUAAAUAGUCUGUAACAUUGAUUAGAUAUCAAGCAACGUGAGCAUGGUAGCAAAAGCACUAACUGAAGCCAGUGAUUUAAUUUUUAAUUCUGAUUCUGAUAAUUGAUGAUAUAGCUCCUCGAACUUUGUUUUUUGUUAAAACUUGGAAAAUAUAUUUGUAUUAUUUUGGACAAAUUAUUUGAACUCUCUGGACCUUGAUUCAAUUUAUAUAUAAGGUAAAGGCAUUAUACUGGAUUAUCCUGCAAUUUCUUUGAGUUGUUAGAAUAUAAUGUAGCUUAUUAAUAGCAAUAUUAGCAGUGUAGUAGAUUCUGACUGCAAAACCUAGCCUUUUCUAUUGAUUCAUUAGUGGUAGUAAAGGUAUUAUCUGAUUUAUCCUUUUUAAUAGGCAGUGCUUUGAUCAAGUGGGAAAUAGUAAUGGACAAAUAAAAUCAAUGAUCAUUAUCUAACUUGAUGCCUGCUUUUCAAAAAGUGAGCAAAUUUCACAUCUUCACCCUUAGACAUUAAUUCAUGGCACCUACUAUAAGUACUCAUCCUCUUCUUACCUAUCUUCUUUUCUAUAGGAGAUAAAGUGGUUAUUCAGACCCCCCAAUACAAUUUUUUGGUUUGUUUUCACAGCUACUUAAAAGAUUAAAAUAACUAUUCUUGCAGAUAUUUCUAGGAAUAUUUUUAGAAAUAAUAUGAAAUACAGGGAUAAUAGGCCAAUUAUGAUCUUUAUUUUUAAUUUCUACAGAAAAGUACUAGAGAAUAUAUCUAUAGAAACUUCUUUCAGAUAACCCUAAAGAUGAUACUAGAAUGUUUAUAAAAUUAUUGAGAAGAUUAUUUGUGUUAUAAAGCUUAUUUGUACCAUAGUAAAGGAUGUUUUUGUUCCUCUUCAUUCUGGGCUAAUCUGUCAAUACUGAAGUCCAGUCUUUUCCCCCUUUUCUUACCAGCUCAACCUUGAUUCCUGUGACCCAUUCUUUCUGAUCUUUCGUAGUUCAUAGUCACCAGGCAUGAGUACCUUGGAUAGCCCUCUGAAGUCUGUUACCACCCAGAUUUCCAACUCGGGUUAAUUGGUACUAAUUCUAUUAGCUGGUAUAAAUAAUCCAAAAUCUGUGCAGACUCUGGGAGCAAAAUGUUCUACUCAGUUUGGAAUACUGUGCCUUAAAAUAUAUUUCAUUGUAACAGCACCUUGUAUAUAUAGUUGGCCAAGGACAGAGUUGUUACAAGUUACGUGGAACUUUCAUAGCAAAUCUUGACAGUAAAUACCUUGUUCUUGUAUUAGGUCUAUAUCCUGAAUUGACCUUUAGCAAGAAUCUUUAGAUCUGCUGGAGGGCUGGGAUGGCUUUUGGACUUCAGUGAAAAAGAAUUUCUGCUACUCAUUGUUGAUAACGCUUCAGUACUGUAUAAAUGUUUAUCCUUUUCCACGUAAUUUGUUUUCUAUGAUAUGAGAACUUUUAUUAUAAUUUGCCUCAGUCUUGAUAGAAUCUUAACAAAAAUAAAAUCUGUGGUCGUCUGAGGUAUUCUCCAUGCUAUAACCCAGUUUAGCUGAUGCAUUUGGAGCUUGGGUGCUGAAAUUAAAUAUAACCUAUUUGAGUUAAGGAUUUAUUACUAGUGCUCCAGUGGUCACAGGAACAAUAAAAAAGGAACAACGAUAGAAAUACGUGAUCUAGGAAAGAAGGCAACUGAAAAACCUGAAAGAAAAAAAAUGAAAGAUUAAAAGUAUACGAUAUUCUAUUUUGAUUUAGCAAUUACUUGUUUUCUAGUGUUCUGUCAAUUUUUGGUGACUUUUAUAAUUACAUUAAAACUAAGAUGCUGAAUUAAAAUAAAGUUUCUCUUUUAUUCAAGCACCAACAUUCACUUAUAUUACCUAUAUAUUGCAUCAAGUUUUGAGCCUUCAAUCCCAGAAGCAUUGAUUGACUGUCUACUGUGGUUCAAGUACUGUGCAUAAAGAUGAAUAAAUAUUCUGUCCUUGGCUUAGUCUAAUAGUAAAGGCACUCUUAGAGGAGGGACAAAUAUUUUGCCUAGAUAAGAUUUGAGAGAUAGUAAGUGCGGAAUUUCUCUUCAUAAAAAUGGUAGUGUUAGUUGUUUAGAGGGAGAAGUCCAGCUAUGUAAGGUGAAAGUGGGGCUUAUAAAAGUGGAUCUAUUGUUUAAAAAUUAGUACUUUGCUCCUAAAAUUUUUACCUAAGUGUUACAUCCAACAACAGAUGAAAGUAAUUCGACAGUAGCAUCUGCUUUAUUCAUUUCAUAUUUCCAGUGCCUGACAUAUUGCUUGGCAUAUAGUAGUUUAGUGGAUGUGUUUGAUGAAUGAAUGAGUAAAAAUUAUUUUUCAUGUUAAAAUAAAACUUUGAAUUACAUGAGUAUACAACUUUUGUUCCUUCAAAAUACCCAUAUUUGUCAAAUAUGACCGAAUUACGACUUUUUUUCUGUUCCACUAGUUUCUACCUUAGAAGUGACAUUCUGCGUAAGGUAGUGGGGGAUUACUAAGUGAUCAUGACUUUUCUGAAGCAGGUCUUAAAUAAUUAUCUAAGCCUUCAGUCAUUUCAAAAUCUCUGUAGUGUAAAUGAUCACAGGCUCUAAAUCAGAUUGUUGUACAAGGUAAUUGACAUGUCCUGAAAUGUAACAUUCAACAUUAACAGUAGAAACAGGCCUCAUUUCUCCCUCUGGCUUUUAUUGAUCAAUUUUGAUAUUGUCCAGAUCCCAUGUUAAACCACUUGAUUUAGAGAUGACUUAAUUCUAAACUUCCUCCAUUUUUAAUUAAUAAGAUUCAAGGUUGCAGUAAAUUGUUAAUCUUAUUUGGAAUUAUAUUAGAAAGUCGAUAUCGGAAUUGGAACCACACAUCUUUUUCUUAUUGUGGGUACAUGGGAU